AGACGGCAGUGGCUCCUGAGAGCUGGCUGGGGCCAUUUUGGCCCCUCGCCUGUGGCCUUCUGCAGACUUGGCCUGGGAGGGGAUGGGGCAGCUGCGCCAUGUGCACCACCCUUUUCCUGCUCAGCACCCUGGCCAUGCUCUGGCGCCGCCGAUUUGCCAACCGAGUCCAACCAGAGCCCAGCGACGUGGAUGGGGCAGCUAGGGGCAGCAGCUUGGAUGCGGACCCUCAGUCCUCAGGCAGGGAGAAAGAACCUCUGAAGUAAGCCCUCACCUCUGCAGGUGGGGCUCAGGCCCAGAGACUGGGAUCAGCUGGCUCAGGCAGCUCAGGUCCUGGUUCGUCCCCUAGCCCAGGAGGAUGCUGUGGGAGCUGCAGCAGCGGCAAGAGGGAGAAUGGGGGGAAGCAGCACUAGAGAAGUUCCCAGAGCUCAUCCUGUCACUGGCUGCUCUGCUGAAAUUAUCAAUAAGAAAUGCCAGUUGGAUCUGUGACAUGUCUGCCUGCAGCUGGAUGGGAGCAACGGACAGCUUGUCCUCCGAAUGUGUUUUCUGUAUGUGUGCAAGCGCGUGUGUUCCAAACGGGCAGUAGCGUGUGGGAAGGAAAAAGCCUGACACUUGUUUUUAUCAAUUUGCUGAUGCUCAGUCCCGGCGGCUGCCUCCUUUGCCCCCAGCUGCUCUGCCAUUUCUCUCUUUUCAAUCCUGCAUGAUCCUGAGCAGAGAUAAAAGCAGAUUUCCGCUUCUGCUCCCAGAUCCAGGAGCAGACCCUGCAGGCAGCUGCUCCUGAUGUCUCACAGCUAUUAGUCUUCAAAAACCCCCCGUGCCUCUGUGCACACGCGUCUCUCCUCCCCAGCCAGCCCCCCUCCCAGCCCAGCGGCGAUGUCUCUGCCUGGCUGGCCCGUGCCCUUGACUUCCAGGCAGUAGAAGAUGGAGUUCUCUAGACAGCAGCACUUCAGCCGCCACUCUGCCUCUGAAGGGAAGGAAGGGAAAGGGGUGCUGGCUACUGUGAAAUAACAAGAGUCCAAGAGCAAGGUGUCCAGAGUCAGAGCUCCUGGGUUUGAACCUUGUUCCACCAGCACAUCCUACCUCUGUGGCCUGGGUAAGUUUCUGAACACCUCUGUGCCUCAGUUUCUUUAGCUGUAGGAUGGAGAUCCUACUGGUAUCUGUCUCUUAGAGUUGUAAGGGUUGAUUAGAUAACGUGUGGAAGAUGCUUAGCAUGUUGGGUAAGUGUCCCAUAUAUGUGAGCUGGCACAAUCCGGUUUGAACUGUAAAUUACUGAACAGUGGUAGAUUCAGGACGGCUAGAGUUCCUCACAUCCUCACUCUCUGGUCCUUCCUGCCGUCUCUCCACAUACACAGAGCUGGGCGACCGGUAGUUCUGCAACAGAUCAGAGGAUGGCAGAGGGUGGCAUUGCUGGGGUGGGGAAGCCCCCUGUAAGCCUGUACUGGAGAAGACCACCACUGCCUCUCUGUGCCCAGAACCAUGUCCCAACCUCCAGUGGUGACCUCGACCUGGACAGCGCCACUCCCAGCUGGCUCUGCUUCCGGAAUGAACCUCAGCUCCUUGACAAGACGGGAGGCGCUGCCCUGCUGUGGUACCUUCCUCCGUGUGAAUGCUAAUAUCUCUGCUGGGGGAGCCUGAGUGACGGGGAAAGGCUGCUUGGAGCUGCAGGGCGGCUGAGGGCAGCAACCAGGAGCAGGGAGGUGCUGCUCCUGCAACUGAGGCUCAGAGCGGCUGCCAGUCUCUCCUGGAGACUGGAGCAUGACCAGGGAACUAAUGAGGCGGUGGGGGUGUGGUGGGAGCCAGGGAAGUAGCCACUGCAGCUGUGGCUGUCCACUGUCACCCUGGGGUGUAGAUGUCACCUUGGGGAGUACCCACCCAUUCCAAGUGUGCGGUUGUGUGUGUGUGUGGUUUGUGUGUGUGUGUGUGUGUGUGCGCGCAGUCCUGGGCAAGGGCAAACAGUACAGGUGGUGGGCCAAGACUAGAUGGGUAGGGCACAGUGCCCACUAUGAGACAGGCACAAUGGCGAGAGAGCAAACCCUGCUGGUUCCUCAGGCUCCCGUAGCCUCUCUGUGGGGGGCCUCACUGUUAGGAAGAAGCCCAAGACCUAGAGCUAGAGGAAGAUAAUGCUUCUUUGUGAACCUCAGAAGAACAGUUUGGUUCGCACGGAAGCUUAUGUUAACAUAAUGAUGAUACUAAUCGUAUGAUUAAUAACCACUAACAUGCAUUGGGCGCUUACUAUGUGCUAGGCACUGUGCCAGCUGCUGUAUUUUACGCACUGUUUCAUUUAUGCGGCAGGAACUGUUAUCAUUUAUCCAAUAAGGAAAGUGAGGUUCACAGAACUUGCUCAAGGUCACUCAUAGCUGGCAGUGAAGCCAGGACCUGAGCCUGGGAAAUCUGACACCAAAGCUUGGGAUAGAGGGGGCCCAAGUCUCGAGUUGGGGGCCGUGAGGAAAUUUUGAUUGUGACCUGUCUACAAGGCACAAGGAAUGGAGCUGUGGUCCCGCCCAGCCUGCCUUUGCAAGUGGGCUGGUGUUGGCCAGGGUCAUUGCCACCAAUCUGUCUUCAGGAACUCACAUUCAAGGGCAGACCAGACUCUAGGCCCUGAGAGGCUGGUUCUUGCCUGCCAGGUGAGGGGGAGAGGAGAGCUGCCCCUUUAGGACCCCUCAGUCUUCCUCAGGAAGGAUGUGGUGGCCUCUGGCAGGGAUGACAGACAGCGAGGUCAUCACCCACAGUCACUGCAACUGCCACUCUGUUGCCUCCUUCAGCCAGGGGCAGGGCCCUGGGGAGAGGACAGGAUGGCAGCCAGCAGCCCAGCUGGAGAUGCGGAGCCUGUCCUUCAGCUCCUACUUAAUGGAAGCCUCGCAGAUGCAAGAUGGCUCCAGCAGGCCCAGCAUCACUUCUUCUCAGUGUCCCAAAGCCAGAAGAGAGGCUGUUGUUUUUAAAAGCAGGAAAACUUUCCUAAACUUGGCCAGAAUUGCAUCACAGACCCUUUCCUAAAACAAUUUCCAGCAAAGGGAAUAGACUUACCAUGUCUGGUACAGAUGAAUCAAGGUUUGCCCCUGGGGGCUGGGGAGGGGCUUGUCCCGCUGAAGCAGACUCUUGCCCAGCAGCUGAACGAAGCCUAGGUUCACCAGACGGAGGAAGAGACUGGCCACUAACAGUGCCUGACACACAGAUGUGCUUCCUGUGAUAUCGCUGCUGCCACCGUUCCAAAUGUAAGCAGUUGGCUGUCUGGGAUACUACCUACCUUCUUUUGUGUUCUUAUUAAUAAAAUUAAAGAUUGCUUUCUGGGUAGAGAAAUUAA